GAAGAGGCCGGGCUACGUCGUGCCCUGCGCGUGAGCAGCUGCAGAGGCAGAGGCAGCAUCCAGCGGCGGCGCCAGCAGUUCCAGUCCGUUGCUUUACUUUUUGCUUCACCGACAUAGUCAUUAUGCCGAAGAGAAAGUCUCCAGAGAAUACAGAGGGCAAAGAUGGAUCCAAAGUAACUAAACAGGAGCCCACAAGACGGUCUGCCAGAUUGUCAGCGAAACCUGCUCCACCAAAACCUGAACCCAAACCAAGAAAAACAUCUGCUAAGAAAGAACCUGGAGCAAAGAUUAGCAGAGGUGCUAAAGGGAAGAAGGAGGAAAAGCAGGAAGCUGGAAAGGAAGGUACUGCACCAUCUGAAAAUGGUGAAACUAAAGCUGAAGAGGUACUUUCCAUAAAUACCUCCCACUGAUUGAAUCAGUGUCUUUAAAGAAAUUUCUCAAUCCUUCAGCCGGUGAUAGCACGUUCUUAAUGUCUCUUUUUAUUGCCUGUAAUGUUAUUGCAGAUCCACAUCUCUCGCUCAACUGUUAAUGUCUCAACCUCCAGAGGCACCCCACCCAGCACACUGUCAGUAAAGGGGCAGAUUGAAACAGUGAGAGUUAAGGGUACAGUAGAAAAUUCUGCAUGUUUGCAGUGACUAGAAUCAGAUAGUAGUGUGGUGGUUUUUUUUUUUAAUCAUUAUGAAGAGUGGGAGCUUGCAGGUAAGGCUUCUGUGGUGGUUUGAAAAGCAGAAAGCAAUAAAUGAAACAAAGUGUUUGUGUAAUAUAUUCCUGCCUUGUCUUCUUCACUCAGAGUUGAAAUAGGUUUUGCAGUAAAGCUGGAAAAAAAAAAGAAAACAAAUGUUCAAAACUGUGUGUGUUGGUGGGUGGAAUUUCCUUUGCUUAUAGUAGUUUCAGUAGUAACUAUAUGUUUUUUUUUCCUUUCUUUUUCACAGGCACAGAAAACUGAAUCUGUAGAUAACGAGGGAGAAUGAAUUGUCAUGAAAAAUUGGGGUUGAUUUUAUGUAUCUCUUGGGACAACUUUUAAAAGCUAUUUUUACCAAGUAUUUUGUAAAUGCUAAUUUUUUAGGACUCUACUAGUUGGCAUACGAAAAUAUAUAAGGAUGGACAUUUUAUCGUCUCAUAGUCAUGCUUUUUGGAAAUUUACAUCAUCCUCAAGUAAAAUAAAUAUCAGUUAAAUAUUGGAAGCUGUGUGUAAGAUUGAUUCAGCAUUCCAUGCACUUGCUUUAAAAUUUAGUCCUGUGCAUACUGUGGUGUUUUUACUGUGCAUAUUUGAAUUUUUCAUGCAGUUUUUCUAGAGCAAUAAUCAGUGGUGCUUUUGUACCUAGGUUUUAUGUGAUUUUAAUGAAACAUGGAUAGUUGUGGCCACCUGCUGACUAUUUGUGGUUUAAAAUAAAAGGUUUACUUGUCUGCAGAA